GAGGUCACGCCCCGACCUGAGGAGAGCUGGCGCCCAGACCCUUCCCCCGGGGAGGAGGGCUCCCGCGCGAAGCCGUCUCCGAAUGCGUCCAGUCGACUCACCGUCCCCGCAGCCCUGGGGCAGCGGCCGCAACAGCAGGACCGAACGCCUCGGCAGCUGGCAGUCGCACUUCUGUCACAAGGAGGCGGUUCCCCUGUCUUGAUACAUUGGCUCUAUCUGGGCAGCCAGGAAGAAGAACCCACUGGGUGGCUACUUGCUCAGAAACAGGGUCUCACUAUGUUGCCCAGGCUGCUCUCGAACUCCUGGCUUCAAGCAGUCCUCCCGCCUUUGCCUCCCCAAAGUGCUGGGAUUACAGGCCUGAACCCCCACACCCACCCAGCCAGUACUUCAGAUUCUUAUCUCUUUGUAAAACCUGGGUCUUCCUAACUCCAAGAAACCUGUCUUCUGCCCGGAUUCGAGAAAAUUCCAAGGAGGGAGCUGCCUCUCCAUCCCUUCCAUAUGUGCUUCUAGGAAAAAGUUACCAGUCUCACAUCACCAGAGGGCUUGAAUGAAGAGGCUGCCAUCAGCUAUUCAAACAUUCAUCCAAUAUUAACUGAGCACCUACUCUGGGUGAGGCUUACCAGGGAGCACCUGCCCCACUCCAGACUUUGAAUUGCGCCCGUUUCAUCACAUUCUUUGGUGUCCUGGCAACCAGAGACUCUGAUCUGAGCUCCAGCCAGAACAGAGGCCAUUCCUCCCUGACUGCUGUGACUCACCACCACCCCAGGCCUCUGAGGACCAGUCCAUGUAGCUCUCGGAACCACUGAAAGCUACCCCUUGUCCUUGAGGACACCUGGAACCCCAGCCCCACUGACCCACCCUGGCAGGAUGAGCUUCUCACUCACGUUCACCGAGCUGGCCAACAUCGCCAUCCCACAGUGCGGGGUGCUGAACUUCAAGGCCCUGCACCUCCUGCUGCACGGCAUCUUGGAGCACAUCCACAUGGCCGAGCUCAAGAAAGUCCUCUCAGGCGAUGAGGACUUCCUGCAGACCUCGCAGGUGGUCAUCAUGCCCAGGGAAGGAGACGCCCAGCCUAUCCUCAACCCCAUGAAGAGGCUCAGCAAUGUCUUCGACCACGUGGUGAGCCGCCUCGACAAGUUGGAGAACCAGCUGGCCCUGCUGCAGGACCUGCCCUCCACUGCCCAGCUGCUGGAAGCCAGCCAGGGCACUGCCCGGCCCGUCCAGGACCUGUGGCAUCUGAUCAAGCUCCGGAAGAUGGUGGAGGGUCAUGAUGAAGUCAUGGCCAAGUCAAUGCAGACCCUGCAGGACUUGCUCACUGAUCUUCAUGCACUCCAGGUCACCAUCACAGCCCUCAGAAAAGAAGUGGACAUGCUGAAGAACAUGCUUGACAAGGUACACCCAGAAAGAAUGGACAUCUUUGCUGAAGACUUCAAAAUACAGAACUGGAAGAUGGUUGCACUGCAGCGGGAAGUGGCUUCUCUCCAGAAUAAGUUUAAAACCAUCCCCAAAACCGAGGACAUGGUGCUCUGGAGUGGCCUUCAUGAUGCCAUGUUCACCUCAGAAAUUGGUUCAUCACCACUGGACCUGUGGCAGUCUGUAGAGCAGCUCCCAGAGGCUGCCCUGGCCCAGACCACCAAGUACCUUGAAGCUACUCGUGCCAUCCAGGUCUCCGAGCCCGUCCAAAACCCCCAGCUACUGCAGACUGUCUGGCAUUAUGAGGUCCCAGAGCUCCUCCCGGAGGGCUCAUCUGCCCAAGCAGUUUCACUCAGCAGAGCCCAGGAGCCAGCGCAGCCUCCGGCCCUCACGCCUGAGUCUGCACCUGGGUGCACAACUGAAUUUGCACCUGGGCCUGCACCUGGGACUGAACCUGUGCCAGGACUGGAGCUGGGGCUGGAGCUGGAGCCUGUGCCUGCCCUGGGGCCUGUCCCAGGGCCCAGUGUGACACCUGGGUCCUUGCCAGCACCUUGGCCUGUGCUUGGACCUGUGCCUGCCCCAGGUGCCCAGCCUCCACCACUGGGAGACUGGCCUGCACUCCCAAGACGCUGGCCUCUUCCCCAAGGCUGGCCCAGGGUGGGCUCUUGGCCUCUGUGGGACUUAGGUGUCCUGCGGCCAACUCAGCCCCAACCCUCCAGGGCCCCACCACCAGCCACUGAGUUUGGCUCAUUGUGGCCUCGACCACUCCAGCCAUAUCAGUCUCGCCAGGGAGAAGCCCUCCAGCUCGCAGCUGUCCAAGUAAAGGGGGAGGAAAAUGAUGUCCCCAGCCUAAGGGGCCUUCGGGAGAGGGCCCGCAAGGAUGGGGCCCCCAAGGAUAGAACUCGCAAGGAUGGGGUCCCCAAAGAUAGAGGUGGCAAGGAUGUGGACCCCAAGGAUAGAGCUCACAAGGAUGAUGUCCCCAAAGAUAGAGGUGGCAAGGAUGUGGACCCCAAGGAUAGAGCUCACAAGGAUGAUGUCCCCAAAGAUAGAGGUGGCAAAGAUGGGGACCCCAAGGAUAGAGUUGGCAAGGAUGGGGCCCCCAAGGAAGCACAGCCUAAGGCUCCCCAGUCUGCCCUUCACCGGCUGAAAACCACCGCUGCCAUCGCCGCCGCUGCCGCCGCAGCCUACGCCGCUGCCACAUCCUCCGCUGCCCAGGCAGCCAAAGUUGCUGCCAAGUUUGUCAAGGAUGCCCCAGCCACCAAAAUGGCCGCCAUUGCAACAGACACGGCUGCAGCUGGGCCCCUAGGGGUCUUUGCAGAUGUCCUGGGUGCAGGGCCUUCCCGGGGAGCCACAGAAUCCCAGAUCUUGGGCGAUGAUUCCGAAAUCUACGAAAUCCUCUCUCCCUCCUACUCUGCUGCCAGCAUCGGUCCCGAUCCAGCCCUGUCCCAGGCCAUGGUGGCUACCAAGCAGGCCAUGAGCCCUGAAGACAAGAAGAGGGCUGUCAAGUAUUCCAUGAGCCACAUAGCCCAGAUACCUGUCAAACACGACUCUCUGAAGGAAGAAUUUGCCCAGCUGUCCUGUAACCUGAACCAGCGCUUGAGUUAUCUAGCCAAUAUGGGAGGUCCUUCCAGCCUCGGGACAACAGUGGACAUAUUGCAGAAAAAGAUUGGCAGCCUCCAGAAAUCUAGGCUCAAGGAGGAAGAACUUGAGAGAAUUUGGGGCAACCAAAUAGAGAUGAUGAAGGAUCGCUACAUCACUUUGGACAAGGCGGUGGAGAACCUGCAGAUUCGCAUGGAUGAGUUCAAGACUCUCCAGGCUCAAAUCAAAAGACUGGAAAUGAACAAGGUGAAUAAGAGCACGAUGGAGGAGGAGCUGAGAGAGAAAGCUGACAGGAGUGCCCUGGCAGGCAAGGCAAGCCGCGUUGACCUGGAGACUGUGGCCUUGGAGCUGAACGAGAUGAUUCAGGGCAUACUCUUCAAGGUCACGAUCCAUGAGGACAGCUGGAAGAAGGCUAUGGAGGAGCUCAGCAAGGACGUGAACACCAAGUUAGUCCACAGUGAUCUGGAUCCCUUGAAGAAAGAAAUGGAAGAGGUCUGGAAAAUCGUCCGGAAGCUGCUGAUUGAGGGCUUAAGACUGGAUCCUGACAGUGCUGCUGGCUUUAGGAGGAAGCUGUUCAAGCGCGUGAAGUGCAUCUCCUGUGACCGGCCUGUGGAGAUGAUGACUGGCCCACAGCUGAUCACCAUCCGCAAAGCCCACCUGCUGUCCCGGCUGCGGCCAGCCAGCGCCAACAGCUGCGAGUACUUGCAGCGGCAACAGAUGAGGGAACAGCAGUGGCUGCAGCUCCAGGACCUCGGUAUCCAGGAGGAUUGUCAGCAGGACUGGGGUGAUGGCCCCCAAAACGCCACCAGCCUCAAGUGCAAGUCCUGCAACCUGUUGACGCUCUAUCCCUACGGGGAUCCCCACGUGAUCGACUAUGACAGCGCCGAGGUGGACAUCCUGGGCGUGGAUGGGAUCCUGUACAAAGGCCGCGUGAACAGCCAGCGUGGGGCUCAGCCCUUGGCCGUCGCAAAGGAGCUGGCAGCUGUGAAGGCUCCAUCUCCCCCGUCACAAAGCCUGUAUGACCGUGUGCACUCCAGUGCCCUAUUUGGCGCCAUCUGCCCCCCCCUGUGCCCCCGCUCCAGUGCCUGCUCAGCUGCCUCGGGCCCUCACCUGACGAUGCCAGCUCGACCACCUUCCCUGCCACCUCUGCUGCUGCUGCCACCGCUGAUUCCAUCCCUAAGGGACCCCCAGCAGGCCCCAGGGUCCACCAGGCUCUCAAGAGCUCCACACAUUGAGUCCCGAGUCGGCAGGAAGCCCCCCGAGGAGCCCGCCAACCCGUGAGCCCCACCCCGCUGCGCCCCCCAUCGCCAAGUCCCCUCCACGUCCGAGGCUGAGGCCCAUGUGGCCCUCCCACUCCCACCAAGUCCCCUCCACAUCGGAGGCUGAGGCCUAUGUGGCCCCCCACCCCCACCCCCACCAAGUCCCCUCCAUGUCCGAGGCUGAGGCUCAUGCGCCCCCCCCCAUCCCUACCAAGUCCCCUCCACGUCCGAGGCUGAGACCCAUAUGCCCCCCCCACCCCCACCAAGUCCCGUCCCCGGCUGAGACCCAGGGCCCUGAGCCUGGCCCAGAAAGGGUGCUGGGGCCCUGGAUAGAGGGGAGGGGUCUGUGUAGGGGACCCCCAUGCUGACCCAGUGGCUGUUUUAUCCUGUGCAUAUAAAUACAAACAGCACAGUGCACAUUCUCAUUCUACAUUGUCAUAUAAACACAGCUUUCUAGAGUGAA